CAGGUCUGCAGUGCCCUGUGCUCCCUCGGGGAGGCGCGGCCGGUGGAGACGCUCCGUGCCUGCGAGGAGUAUCUGCGGCAGCAUGACAAGUUGCAUAACCCAUUGCAGACUUGCUGAGUCAGCCUGUCACCCUGCACUGAGCACUCAAUCACCAGGACACAGAGUGACAGAUGGAGAUGCCACAGUUGUGAGUGGAAUCUGGAGAACUCAGUCCCAGGACUCACUUCUCCCUAUUGUUUUCCUCUGGAAAAAAGCAAAGAUUUCCCUCAAACUUCCUCAUAUACAUGAAGAGAAUUAGUAGCUAAAGAUGGAAGCAUAAUGCAACUUGAGAUGUGUUUCCAAGAUCAAGAACCAGAGGAGAUGGCAGCUGUGGGUCUGGUCAGUUCCUGCACUAUACCGGCCGUGCUGCCCCGGCAGUUAAUCCACCCACUUAGAGCCUCAGCUCUGCGACGUCCCAGCUGGCACACCCAUACCGAGCAGCGGUCCUGAGGGCCAUGGAGAGGGUCCUGAGCAGUCGCGCCAGUGAGCUGGACAAGGACACAGCCAGCACCAUCAUCCUCCUGGCCUCCAGCGAGAUGACCAAGACGAAGGACCUGGUCUGGGACUGGCAGCAGGCGGCGAGUGGCGUCCUGGUGGCCGUGGGAAGACAGUUCAUCAGCAAGGUGAUGGAGGAGCUGCUGCGCAGGCUGCACCCUGGGACCCUGCCACACUGCGCCGUGCUGCACACCCUCGCCAGCCUCUCGGUGGCCAACGCGUUCGGCGUAGUCCCCUUCCUGCCAUCCGUCCUGAGCUCCCUGCUGCCCGUGCUGGGCGUGGCCAAGCAGGACACGGUGCGCGUGGCCUUCUGCUCCGCUCUGCAGCGCUUCAGCGAGGGUGCCCUGGAGUACCUAGCCAACCUGGACCGAGCCCCAGACCCCACGGUCAGGAAGGACGCCUUUGCCACCGACAUCUUCAGCGCCUACGAUGUUCUCUUCCAUCAGUGGCUGCAGAGUCGAGAAGCCAAGCUCCGUCUUGCCGUGGUGGAGGCUCUGGGGCCUAUGAGCCAUCUGCUGCCCAGUGAGAGGCUGGAAGAGCAGCUGCCCAAGCUCCUCCCUGGGAUUCUCGCCCUCUACAAGAAGCACGCAGAGACCUUCUACUUGUCCAAGAGCCUGGGCCAGAUCCUCGAGGCAGCUGUGAGUGUGGGCAGCCGCACACUGGAGACCCAGCUGGAUGCCCUCUUGGCUGCACUGCACUCCCAGAUCUGUGUGCCUGUGGAGUCCUCAAGCCCCCUGGUGAUGAGUAACCAGAAGGAGGUGCUGCGCUGCUUCACUGUGCUGGCCUGCAGCUCGCCUGACCGCCUACUGGCCUUCCUGCUGCCCAGGCUGGACACCAGCAAUGAGAGGACCCGCGUGGGCACCCUGCAGGUGGUCAGACAUGUCAUCAACUCAGCUGCUGCUCAGAUGGAAGAUAAAAAGCCCUUUAUCCUGUCUUCCAUGAGGCUUCCUCUCCUGGACACCAACAGCAAGGUGAAGCGGGCAGUGGUGCAGGUGAUUAGCGCCAUGGCCCACCACGGCUACCUGGAGCAGCCUGGAGGUGAGGCGAUGAUCGAGUACAUCGUGCAGCAGUGCGCGCUGCCCCCCGAGCAGGAGCCUGAGAAGCCAGGCCCCGGCAGCAAGGACCCCAAGGCCGACAGCGUGCGGGCCAUCAGCGUGCGCACCCUCUACCUGGUCAGCACCACCGUGGACAGGAUGAGUCACGUCCUCUGGCCAUACCUGCUCCAGUUCCUCACCCCUGUGCGCUUCACUGGGGCCCUGACUCCGCUCUGCAGGAGCCUCGUGCAUCUGGCGCAGAAGAGGCAGGAGGCCGGGGCCGACGCCUUCCUCAUCCAGUACGACGCCCAUGCGAGCCUCCCGUCUCCCUAUGCUGUAACCGGAAGACUGUUGGUUGUGUCUUCCAGCCCCUACCUAGGGGACGGACGUGGGGCAGCGGCGCUGCGCCUCCUCAGUGUUCUGCACCCAAACAUUCACCCUUUGCUGGGUCAGCAUUGGGAAACGACUGUCCCGCUGCUGCUGGGGUACCUGGAUGAGCACACAGAAGAGACCCUGCCACAGGAGGAGUGGGAGGAGAAGCUGUUGAUGUUCCUGCGAGACACCCUGGCCAUCAUUUCUGACAACGCGUGGAUCUGCCAGCUGAGCCUGGAGCUGUGCAGGCAGCUGCCCUGCUACGAUGAGGCACCCCAGGAGAAGAACUUCCUGUACAAAUGCAUAGGCACCACCCUGGGUGCUGCUUCAAGUAAGGAGGUGGUGAGGAAGCACCUUCAAGAGCUGCUGGAGACGGCCAGAUACCAGGAGGAGGCAGAACGCGAGGGCCUCGCCUGCUGCUUCGGGAUCUGUGCCAUCUCCCACCUCGAGGACACGCUGGCCCAGCUGGAGGACUUCGUGAGGUCAGAGGUCUUCAGAAAAUCCAUUGGCAUUCUCAACAUUUUUAAGGAUCGAAGUGAGAACGAAGUGGAGAAGGUGAAGAGUGCUCUGAUCCUGUGCUAUGGGCACGUGGCGGCCCGGGCCCCCCGGGAGCUGGUGCUGGCCAAGGUAGAGUCAGACAUCCUCCGGAACAUCUGCCAGCACUUCAGCACCAAGGUUCUAGGAAUAAAGGUAGAAACCAAGGACCCAGCCCUGAAGCUGUGCCUUGUCCAGAGUGUGUGCAUGGUCAGCCGCGCCAUCUGCAGCAGCACCCAGGCUGGCUCCUUCCACUUCACCCGGAAAGCAGAGCUGGUGGCACAGAUGAUGGAGUUCAUCAGGGCAGAGCCCCCGGACUCCUUGAGGACACCUAUUCGGAAGAAAGCCAUGCUCACCUGCACUUACUUGGUCUCCGUGGAGCCAGCGCUGGACGAGCAGGCCCGGGCGGAUGUGAUCCAUGGCUGCCUGCACAGCAUCAUGGCCCUGCUGCCUGAGCCCAAGGAGGAGGACGGAGGCUGCCAGAAGUCCCUGUAUCUGGAGACACUGCACGCCCUUGAGGAUCUGCUGACGAGCCUCCUGCAGCGGAACAUGACCCCCCAAGGCCUGCAGAUCAUGAUUGAGCACCUGAGCCCAUGGAUCAAGUCCCCAAGAGGUCACGAGCGGGCGCGGGCCCUGGGCCUGAGCGCCCUCCUGCUGCGCUACUUCCUGGAGCACCUGCGUGUCAGCGCCCUGGUGCCCUUCCACAACCUGGGCCUUCUCAUCGGCCUCUUCUCCCCACGGUGUGCGGACCUGUGGCCUGCCACCCGCCAGGAGGCCGUGGACUGUGUCUACUCCCUGCUGUACCUCCAGCUCGGCUAUGAGGGCUUCUCCCGGGACUACCGCGAUGACGUGGCGGAGCGGCUCCUCAGCCUCAAGGACGGCCUCGUGCACCCUGACCCCGCCAUUCUCUUCCACACCUGCCACAGUGUAGGCCAGAUUAUUGCCAAGCGCCUCCCCCCAGACCAGCUCAUCAGCCUCUUGCUAACCAUGUUUGAGGCCCUGGGAGACCCCGAAAAGAACUGCUCCCGAGCAGCUACCGUCAUGAUCAACUGCCUGCUGCAGGAGCGGGGCGGUGUGCUCCAGGAGAAGGUGCCCGAGAUCGUGAGCGUCCUGCGCUCCAAGCUUCAGGAGGCCCAGGGAGAGCACGUCCUGCCGGCCGCCCAGCACAGCGUGUACCUCCUGGCCACCCAGCACUGCGCAGCCGUGGUGUCCAGCCUCCUGGGCAGCCCCUUGCCCUUGGACAGCCACACCUGCAUGCUGUGGCGGGCGCUGGCGGUGGAGCCUCGCCUAGCUGCCCAGGUCCUGGGGCUGCUGCUGGAGAAGAUGAGUAGGGACGUCCCUUUCAAGGAGAGCCGGGCCUUCCUGCUGGGCCGCACCCCAGACCGCGUGGCCACGCUGCUGCCUCUCUCGGCUACCUGUGCACUGUUUGAGGUCAUGUCCACGCCUGCAGCGGGGCCCGCGGUGCUCGAGCUCUACCCCCAGCUGUUUGUGGUGCUUCUGCUGCGCGUCAGCUGCACCGUGGGUGUCCAGCUGCCCCGGAACCUGCAGGCCCAGGAAAGGAGGGGUGCCAGUCCAGCCCUAGCCACCAGGAACCUGGAACCCUGCAGCUCUGCAGUGGACACCCUGCGGUCCAUGCUACUCCGCAGCGGCAGCGAGGAUGUGGUACAGCGCAUGGACCUGGAGGGAGGCUGGGAACUGCUCAGGACCUCGGCGGGGCAUGAGGAGGGGGCCACCAGGUUGGCCAGGGCCAUGGCUGAGCACGCAGGGCCCCGACUCCCCCUGGUGCUGAAGACGCUGGCAUGCACACACAGCAGUGCGUAUGAGAACCAGAGGGUGACCACCACCGCCUUCCUGGCCGAGCUGCUGAACAGCAACGUGGCCAACGACCUCAUGCUCUUGGACUCGCUGCUGGAGAGCCUGGCGGCUCGCCAGAAGGACACAUGCGCCAGCGUGCGGAGGCUGGUGCUCCGCGGCCUGGCCAACCUGGCCUCCGGCUGCCCUGACAAGGUGCGAACCCACGGCCCCCAGCUCCUCACAGCCAUGAUUGGCGGGCUGGACGACGGGGACAACCCUCACAGCCCAGUGGCCCUGGAGGCCAUGCUGGGCCUUGCGAGGCUGGUGCACCUGGUGGAGUCCUGGGACCUGCGCUCAGGGCUGCUGCACGUGGCCAUCCGCAUCCGGCCUUUCUUCGACAGUGUGACCGUGGAGAGCGCGGACCUGCAGGGCUGCUGCUUUGCUGGGCCUGGCAGCCCCCACCCGAGAAGAUGGAGUUCCGGACGGCAUCUAUCCGCCUCUUUGGGCACCUUAACAAGGUCUGCCACGGAGACUGUGAGGACGUCUUCCUGGACCAGGUGGUGGGCGGGCUGGCGCCCCUGCUGCUGCACCUGCAGGACCCUCAGGCCACCGUGGCCAGCGUUUGCCCUGCGCAUGUGUGGCCCCAAUCUGGCAUGUGAGGAGCUCUCAGCUGCUUUCCAGAAACACCUGCAGGAGGGCCGAGCCCUGCACUUCGGGGAGUUCCUCAACACCACCUGCAAGCACCUGAUGCACCAUUUCCCAGACCUGCUGGGCCGUCUCCUGACCACCUGCCUGUUCUACUUCAAGAGCAGCUGGGAGAACGUCCGAGCUGCUGCACCCCUGUUCACCGGGUUCCUGGUGCUGCACUCGGAGCCCAGGCAGCAGCCGCAGGUGGACCUGGACCAGCUCAUUGCGGCGCUCCAGAUCCUGCUGAAGGACCCGGCCCCCGAGGUGCGGACGAGGGCUGCUGAGGCCCUGGGCCGCCUGGUGAAGCUCGCCUAAGGCUCCGGCCAGCACCCCCAGCGAGGAGUAUGCACCCAGACCUGUGCCUGAGCUCCAAGACAGGGCCUCCUGAGGACCACAGCCUGGGCACACGACUGGAGGGGCCUGGCCCCAGAACAGGCACUGCUGGGGACCAAACCCAAGCCCUUCAGUGAGGGAUGUGCCCAAUAAACUCAUCUGCUCCCA